GGGUUGGUGGAUGACCUUGAGCCCUCAGGAACGAGAUGGCGGUUCUCUGGAGGCUGAGUGCCGUUUGCGGUGCCCUAGGAGGCCGAGCUCUGUUGCUUCGAACUCCAGUGGUCAGACCUGCUCAUAUCUCAGCAUUUCUUCAGGACCGACCUAUCCCAGAAUGGUGUGGAGUGCAGCACAUACACUUGUCACCGAGCCACCAUUCUGGCUCCAAGGCUGCAUCUCUCCACUGGACUAGCGAGAGGGUUGUCAGUGUUUUGCUCCUGGGUCUGCUUCCGGCUGCUUAUUUGAAUCCUUGCUCUGCGAUGGACUAUUCCCUGGCUGCAGCCCUCACUCUUCAUGGUCACUGGCUGGAGUGCAAUGGUGCGAUCUUGGCUCGGCACGAUCUCGGCUCAGCACGAUCUCAGCUUACUGCAACCUCCGCCUUUCGGGUUCAAGCGAUUCUCCUGCCUCAGCCUCCCAAGUAGCUGGCAUUACAGGGGCCUUGGACAAGUUGUUACUGACUAUGUUCAUGGGGAUGCCUUGCAGAAAGCUGCCAAGGCAGGGCUUUUGGCACUUUCAGCUUUAACCUUUGCUGGGCUUUGCUAUUUCAACUAUCACGAUGUGGGCAUCUGCAAAGCUGUUGCCAUGCUGUGGAAGCUCUGACCUUUUUGACUUCAUACUUUGAAGAAUUGAUGUAUGCCUCUUUGCCUCUGCUUUGUCAUGCCAUUAAGCUCACAAUAAGGAAGAAAUAACAGAUAAGUCCAUUGGUGGACAGCCUUCUUCUCUUAAUCACAAGAUUAUUUUCAGAAUUUAAUCUUUGAGGAAAAGGUUUGAGAGGAAUUAUAUCUAAGUUGUGAGACUGAGUUCUAUAUUCUGGUGAGUUAAUGGGGUUGCCUCCCAGCUUCUUAUAAGACUCACAGUAUAACUAAACAUGAUAUAUCAGCUUUUGCCUUUCAAUUUAUCAAUCUCUUAAAGAGAAUCCAACUUUAUUACGAUUAGUAUAUGAUCAAACUUCCAUAUUUGCCUUGGGAAUAAUGGACAAAGGGAAAUACUCUUAAUUCAUGAAUAAAAACUUUGCAGAAAAUUAGACAGUGUUUAAUUUUCGAAAACUUCCCUCUCUAGACAGUAGAUACCACCUACUGAUGGUUACAUAUACUAGGGAAAUUUUAAAAUUAGGAAAUGCUGAUAGCUCAUAUUAUAAAUUUCUAAAUCCUAGGAAGAAACGCUUGGAGUGCUUCUGAAUAUACAGAAGUUCCAUUUAAGGGCAAGUUUCCCUGUAGAUGUAUCAAAAUACUACCAACUGUAAAUUGAGAUUUAAUUCCCAAAUGUAUUCUACUUGUUCUAAAACAAUCUGUCCACAAAUAUAAAACUAUAAGUAAUAAAUUGUUAUUUUCGCACAAUGGGAAUCUCUAAUGUGAAAAUGUAUUCUAUGAAAAUAAUUUUUUUAAAUAAAAUGUUAUAUAAUAAAAGUGUCUUCUAUGCUUUUA